CUCUCUCCACUUCCUGCUACUGCAGGCCUCUCCUCCGAGAACAGGUAGGGCCCCCAGGAACCGAGCAUCUGGCAUCUUCAGCCCCUGCUGCCUCCCUUUGGUAUGAGGCAGCUGCCCUGACCCACCCCUGCCACGCACUGCCCACAGCCUCCUCUCCUGCCACGAGGCCAGGUCAUGACUCACUGGCUUCCUGCAACCUGACGAUGGCCCAGCCAGAAGACAAGGCACCUGAAGUCCCCACAGAGGGGGUGAGGCUGGUCCCACCACAGGUGAACAAAGCAGACAGGACCCCUCUAGGGGUCCUCAGCACCCUAGAGCCACUUACUCGCCUGCAGAGGACAUGGGGGGUGUGGCAUGUGCCAGAGCUGGAUACCCAGGAUGCGGAGGCCCUUGUGGGGCUGUGGCCACUAGGGAGUUUCUUGGUCACAGGACGUGACCCCAGCCAGGCCCUGGUGUUGAGGUCAGGACCUUUACCAGGAGAAGUCAAUACCUACCAGAUCCAGAAGAUUCCCAGAGGUGUGUCCCUGGAAUCCUCCAACCUCUGCAUGCCAGACCUGCCCCAUCUCCUGGCCUUUCUAUCAGCCAGCAGGGAUGUUCUGCCCAGAACCCUGCUCUUGCCCCCUCCCACUCUAGGGCCCAGAGAUGAACACACAGAUCCUGUGCAGAUCGGCAGGGUCCAACAGGACACCCCAGGGAAGGUGCUUUCCAUUGUGAACCAGCUCUACCUGGAGACCCACAGAGGCUGGGGGAGGGAGCAGACCCCUCAAGAAACAGAGCCAGAGGCUGCUCAGAGACAUGAUCCAGCCCCCAGGAACCCUGCGCCUCACGGGGUCUCCUGGGUGAAAGGCCCGCUCAGCCCGGAAGUGGACCAUCCUGGGCCGGCUCUCGCCAGCCUACUGGAAGAGGAGGAGGAAGACCUUGAAGGAAAGGAGGAAGGAAGGGAGGACGACCCUGAAGAGGAAGGCCCUGAGGACGUGCUCACCAUUCACGUCCAGUCUCUGGUCAGGGCCCGGAGCAGCUACGUGGCCAGGCAGUACCGAAGCCUUCGGGUGCGCAUCGCCUCAGAUUCUGGGGGUCCCCACGGGUCUGGGGACCCGGCCACGGAGCUGCUUCAGGAUGUGCGGCACCUCCUUACUGACCUCCAGGAUCACCUGGCAAAGGACUCCUACAUCAGGGCUGUCUUUGGAAGCAGGGGUCCUGGGCUCCCCAAGAAGGACGAGGAUCCAGGCCCCGCGCUGGAGACGGCGGUGUGCCAGGCGGUGCUGGCGCCCCUGAAGCCGGCCCUGUGGACACGACUCCGCACACUCCGAGCACCGGAGCUGCGGCGGCUGCGGCGGCGACAGACAGCCCUGCGGGCGGGGGCGGGGCCUCCGGGGGCACAGGGGCCGGGACCGGAAGGGCAGAGCCCCGCCCCCGCCUUGCGGAGCCGCAUCCACGAGCGCCUUGCGCACCUCCACGCUGCCUGCGCCCCGCGCCGCAAGGUGGCGCUCCUCUUGGAGGUGUGCAGAGAUGUCUAUGCGGGCCUGGCUCGAGGCGAGAACCAAGAUCCCCUGGGGGCCGACGCCUUCCUGCCGGCGCUGACCGAGGAACUCAUCUGGAGCCCGGACAUUGGGGACACGCAGCUGGACGUAGAGUUUCUUAUGGAGCUCUUAGAUCCAGAUGAGCUGCGGGGAGAGGCUGGGUACUACCUGACCACGUGGUUUGGGGCGCUGCACCACAUUGCCCACUACCAGCCCGAAACAGACCGCGCUCCCCGGGGGCUCAGCUCCGAGGCCCGCGCCUCCCUGCACCAGUGGCACCGCAGGCGGACGCUGCACAGAAAGGAUCAUCCCAGAGCCCAGGUGACUGCCCAUCUGGCUGCAAGUAGAAGGGAGGGUGAGACCUGGUGCCCUUCUGACCCAGCUCCCACCUCUCCCCACAGGCCAACCUGCCCUUUAAGGAGCCAUGGGCAGAAGAGACUGUGACAGGGACCAGUGACAACUAGGGGUUUCACACCCCUCCGUUCAUGCCUGUAAUCCCAACAUUUUGGGAGGCCAAGGUGGGAGGAUUGCUUGAGCCCAGGAGUUUGAGACCAGCCUGGGCAAAACAGUGGGACCCCCAUCUACCAAAAAAAAAAAAAAACAAAAAUUAGCCGGGCGUGGUGGCGUACUCCUGUGGUACCAGCUACUCAGGAGGCUUUGCAGUUUUAGACAGGCGUAUCAGAGAAAGCCUCACUGAGGUGACAUCUGCAGAAAGGCCUGAAGGAGGGGAGGGGAAGGGAGGAGCAGAGUGGGUAUUAGGAAGAGCAUUCCGAGAAGCAGGAUGAGCCAGUGCAAAGGCCCAGAGGUAGGCUGUUCCCUUUUCCUGGGACCCCUCCCUCCUCCUUGCUGCUCCUAAACCACAUAGGUCAGGAGUCUGGACUGACCCAGGUACGUCUGGCAUCUUGCUUGAGGAACAGGGGGUUUUGUUUUGUUUUGAAAGAACGUCUCUGUCUGUUGCCCAGGCUGGAGUGUAGUGGCAUGAUCUCGGCUCACUGCAGCCUUAACCUCCUGGCUCAAACAAGCCCCCUGCCUCUGCCUACCAAGUAGCUGAGACUACAGGCACCUACCACCGUGCCUGUCUAAUUUUUAAAAUUUUUUAUAAAGAUGAGGUCUCUCUUUGUUGCCCAGGCUGGUCUCAAACUCCUAACCUCAAGCAAUCUGCCCACGUCGGCCUCCCAAAGUGCUGAGAUUAUAGGCGUGAGCCACCGUGCCCAAUUGUGAUCGUUUUUCCCAAAGAAUGUAUCACAUGCUAACAAACCAUAUAUUUAUGUAUUUCAUUGUUCAUAGUAACUACAAUUUAAAAAACUAAAAAGAAACAAGUGAGGCCGGGUGCGGUUGCUCAUGCCUGUAAUCCCAGCACUUUGGGAGGCCAAGGUGGGCAGAUCACCUGAGGUCGGGAGUUCAAGACCAGCCUGACAAACAUGGAGAAACCCGUCUCUACUAAAAAUACAAACUUAGCCGGGCAUGGUGGCGCAUGCCUGUAAUCCCAGCUACUCCGGAGGCUAAGGCAGGAGAAUGGCUUGAACCCGGGAGGCGAAGAUUGCGGUGAGCGGAGAUUGCGCCAUUGCACUCCAGCCUGGGCAACAAGAGUGAAACACCAUCUCAAAAAUAAAUAAAUAAAUAAAAAGAAACAAGUGAAGUUAACGUUAAUAAUAAUAUAUUUGAUUUAACACAAUGUAUCCCAAAUAUUAUCACUUCAACAUGUAUCCAUAUUAAAAAGUUACUGACAUAUUUAAAA